AAGGGUAGGGGAAGUGCGCGGUGAGCGGCCUGGGUCUUGCAGGCUCGGCUGGGGCCCGCAGGUACGUGCAUGGGAGUUUGAAGGGACUGACCAGGCUGGUCUGGAGUGUUGGGCAUGUAUGAGUGUGUCGGGCAUGUAUGAGUUGGUCGGGCUGAUAGAGGGGGUGGUGGGGAGGCGGGCGCGAGGCGUGGGCUUCCGUGUGUGAGUGUGACCUUAUGUGACUGUGCCUCUCUGUGUGCGCGGGUGUGAUUGUAUAUCCUCGUUGUAGUUGUGUAAUUGUAACAAUGUAAGGCUGUAUGUGUAGGUAUGACUGUGUCCCGUGUUGGGACUGUGAUUGUGUGUGGCUGUGUAACUUUGCGUGACAUUUGUGGAGGGUGUUUGUGUGGAGAGAAUCUGAUGAGGCUGUGACUGUGUGUUAGUCUGAGGGGUGUGUGUAAUUGUGUUUGUAUGACUGUUAGCAGCACUUAAGUGUACUGGAUGCCUUACUGAGUAAAUCUACUACCCAGAAAUAACCCAGUAACGUGAGAAUGUGAGAGUGUGACCAUGUAACUUUAUGUAGCACUGUGUCUGCGGUUGGAAAGUGCGUGUAAUCGUGCCGGGGUGAUAUGUGUGUCCUAGUGGUCAUUGUGUUAUUUUGAAUGUGUGAUUGUGUGUAGUGCUCAAUAGGGGUCCUGGGGAGGGGGGAACUGUAACUUUGUGUGGCUCAGUAGUGCGUGUGGUAUUGUGACUAUCUGUAGCACUCUGGUUCUGAAUGGUGCUAUGUUUGAGGGGUCUGUAAAUAUGCUAGUGUAACUUAUCCUCAAGGUAGAUGUGGGACAAUGAUUGUGUGACCAUAUAUAGUGUUAUUGUUUGGGUGAGGCGUGCCUGUGGAGGUCUAUGUGGGUCCCCAUGGUGGCUGGGUGACUGCAGCAUUGGGUAGGGGGUGCUUGUGACUGUCUUUGUGACUCCAGCUCUCCCUGUGAGGUCAGGACAGAUUCUCGAGAGGAGAGACCUCACCCCUCUGAUACCAAGAAUGCUCAUGACAGCCUACACUUCUCUGUUUUUGUUUUGUUUUGUUUUAAGGCGGAGUUUCGCUGUUGUUGCCCAGGCUGGAGUGCAAUGGCGCAAUCUCGGCUCACCGCAACCUCCGCCUCCCCGGUUCAAGCAAUUCUCCUGCCUCAGCCUUCCUAGUAGCUGGGAUUACAGGCGUGUGUCACCACGCCCUGCUAAUUUUGUAUUUUCAGUAGAGACGGGGUUUCUCCGUGUUGGUCAGGCUGGUCUCGACCUCCCCACCUCAGAUAGUAGCUGUAGAUCCAAAAUGACCUCUGAUCUGCUCAGUCUGGGCCACAAGAAAGGCCUGGCAUCUCAUCAUUCCUUUCUUCUUCAGCUCUGCUCUCGUCAAGAGAGUUACCCAGAGGAAGAAUGGCUGUUGACCAAACCAAAUACAAGACGGAGUCUCACUCUGUUGCCCAAGCUGGAGUGCAGUGGCAUGAUCUCAGCUCACUGCAGCCUCUGCUUUCCGGGUUCAAGCGAUUCUCUUGCCUCAGCCUCCUGAGUAGCUGGGAUUACAGGAGAACGGCCUCAAGGAAGACUAACCAUCUGCAAUACUAGAAGCCAUGGCUGAGGGAUCAGUGAUGUUCAGUGAUGUGUCCAUAGACUUCUCUCAGGAGGAGUGGGACUGCCUGGACCCUGUUCAGAGGGACUUAUACAGAGAUGUGAUGUUGGAGAACUACGGCAAUCUGGUUUCAAUGGGACUUUACACUCCUAAGCCUCAAGUGAUCUCCUUAUUGGAACAAGGGAAAGAGCCCUGGAUGGUUGGCAGAGAGCUUACAAGAGGCCUGUGUUCAGAUCUGGAAUCGAUGUGUGAAACCAAGUUAUUAUCUCUAAAGAAGGAAGUUUAUGAAAUAGAAUUAUGCCAGAGGGAGAUAAUGGGACUUACAAAGCAUGGCCUUGAGUACUCCAGUUUUGGAGAUGUUUUGGAAUAUAGAAGCCACCUUGCAAAACAACUGGGAUAUCCAAAUGGGCAUUUUAGUCAAGAAAUAUUCACUCCUGAAUACAUGCCCACAUUUAUUCAACAGACAUUCCUUACUCUCCAUCAAAUAAUUAAUAAUGAAGACAGACCCUAUGAAUGUAAGAAAUGUGGAAAGGCCUUUAGUCAGAACUCACAAUUUAUUCAACAUCAGAGAAUUCAUAUUGGUGAAAAAUCUUAUGAAUGUAAAGAGUGUGGGAAAUUCUUUAGUUGUGGUUCACAUGUUACUCGGCAUCUGAAAAUUCAUACUGGCGAAAAACCCUUUGAAUGUAAGGAAUGUGGAAAGGCCUUCAGUUGUAGCUCAUACCUUUCUCAACAUCAGAGAAUCCAUACCGGUAAGAAACCCUAUGAAUGUAAGGAAUGUGGGAAGGCCUUUAGUUAUUGCUCAAAUCUUAUUGACCAUCAGCGAAUUCACACUGGUGAAAAACCUUAUGAAUGUAAAGUAUGUGGGAAAGCCUUUACUAAGAGCUCACAACUUUUUCAGCAUGCACGAAUUCAUACAGGUGAGAAACCCUAUGAAUGUAAGGAAUGUGGCAAAGCCUUUACCCAGAGCUCAAAGCUUGUUCAACAUCAGAGAAUUCAUACUGGUGAGAAACCCUAUGAGUGCAAGGAAUGUGGCAAAGCCUUUAGUAGUGGCUCAGCACUUACUAAUCAUCAGAGAAUUCACACUGGUGAGAAACCCUAUGAUUGUAAGGAAUGUGGAAAGGCUUUUACUCAGAGCUCACAGCUUCGUCAACAUCAGAGAAUUCACGCUGGUGAGAAACCCUUUGAAUGUCUUGAAUGUGGGAAGGCCUUUACUCAGAACUCACAACUUUUCCAGCAUCAGAGAAUUCAUACAGAUGAAAAACCAUAUGAAUGUAAUGAAUGUGGAAAGGCCUUUAAUAAAUGCUCAAACCUUACUCGACAUCUGAGAAUUCACACUGGUGAAAAGCCCUAUAACUGUAAGGAAUGUGGGAAGGCUUUUAGUAGUGGCUCGGAUCUCAUUCGUCAUCAGGGAAUUCAUACUAAUAAAUAAUAAAAAUUAAAGCCCCUGUCACCUUCCUCAUAUUUUAAACCAAAAAUCAUGUCUAAUAGUUACCCUCUUCCGUAGUUUUUUUUAAAACUUUGUAUUUAAAUUUUGUAUCCAAAUGUAUUUCAUUCCAGGUUAUAAAUUCGGAGUCUAAAGUGACAUUCCCUCUCUCCCCCAGUCAUAUACCGAUGCCAGCUGUUCUAUAAUUCUUUCAUUCAUUGUUUUGUUCUACUUUCUUGGUGACACAUUAUACUCAUGUUUAUAUUUGCUUGUGUUUUUAGAGCUAUCUUUUCUGAUCUGUGUAUUUGUGUUUGCACCAGUAUCACACUGUUUGAAUUGUGUGACCUUUAAUAUUUUUAAAUUCCUUGUGGAGGUUUAACUUUGUUUUUGAAGUUAGUGUUAGUCUUUUUGUUUUAUUUUAUUAUUAUUAUUAUAUGUUUUUUGAGACGGAGUUUCACUCUGUUGCCCAGGCUGGAGUGCAGUGGCGCAAUCUCGGCUCGCUGCAACCUCCACCUCCCGGCUUCAAGCAAUUCUCCUGCCUCAGACUCCUGAGUAGCUGGGAUCACAGGCGUGUGCCACCACACCCUGCUAAUUUUCUAUUUUUAGUAGAGACAGGGUUUCUCCAUGUUGGUCAGGAUAGUCUUGAACUCCUGACCUCAGGUGAUCCACCUGCCUCAGCCUCCCAAAGUGCUGGGAUUACAGGCAUGAGCGAUUGCACCUGGCUUUAUUUUUUGUUGAGACGGAGUUUCGCUCUUGUUGCCUAGGCUGGAGUGCAAUGGUGCAAUCUCGGCUCGUCACAACCUUCGCCUCCCAGGUUCAAGUGGUUCUUCUGCCUCAGCCUUUUGAGUAGUUGGGAUUACAGGCAUGUGCCACAACACCCGGCUAAUUUUUUGUAUUUUUAGUAGAGACGGGGUUUCACCAUGUUAGCCAGGAUGGUCUCAAUCUCCCGACUUCAGGUGAUCCACCCGCCUCGGCCUCCGAAAGUGCUGGGAUUACAGGCGUGAGCCACUGCGGCCGGUCUUUUUAUUUUACAAAUGUACAUUUUUAAUUGUUAAGCCAAAAUCACAAAGCAAAAAAUUACAAACUAAAAAGCCAAAAUUAAUUGUAAUCAUACUUAUAGAUGGCUGCUCUCAAUUUGGUAGAGAAAAUCGUGCUAUACUUUGCUUUUUUAAGAAAGUGUAAUUAUGAUAUGCAUGCUGUACCCUUAACUGCUUUUAUCAUGCCAAAGAUUUCAUGAGUGCCAUUUCAGUAAAUAUAGAUUUUUAUUAUUUUCAUGACAUAUUUAAUGACUUUAAAAUGACUAUUCCCAUUAUGGUUGCCACUAAAUUUUUGCAGCUAUAAAAGCUGACCUCGGCUGGGCACAGUGGCUCAUGCCUGUAAUCCCAGCACUUUGGGAGGCCGAGGUGGGCGGAUCACAAGGUCUGAAGAUUAAGGCCAUCCUGGCUAACAGUGAAACCCCGUCUCUACUUAGCUGGGCGUGGUGGCAUGUACCUGUAAUCCCAGCUACUCGGGAGGCUGAGACAGGAGAAUUGCUUGAACCUGGGAGGCGGAGGUUGCAGUGAGCUGAGAUGGUGCCACUGCACUCCAGCCUGGGGGACAGAGUGAGAUUCCGUCUCAAAAAAACACAAAAACUGCUGACCUCAUUGGAUGCUUAUUUUUACUUUUAAAACAUUUAUUUUAAUUGCUAAAAUUAUCUACAUUUUCUCCUUGUGAGCUGUUUUGUUCCCUUACAUCAAUCCUAAUCCCAAUGCCAUACUAGAAAGUAACACUGUUAUGAAAGUGUUAUUUAUCAAUCCAGAUAUUAAUUUUUUGUUUGUUUGUUUUUUUUUUUUUUUGAGAUGGAGUUCACUCUGUUGCCCAGGCUGAAGUGCAGUGGCACAAUCUCAGUUCACCACAACUGCUGCCUCCCGGGUUCAAGCGAUUCUCCUGCCUCAGCCUUCCUAGUAUCUGAGACUACAGGCGCACGACACCAUGCCUGGCUAAUUUUUGUAUUUUUAGUAGAGACAGGGUUUCACUAUGUUGGCCAGGCUGGUCUUGAACUCUUGACCUUGUGAUCCACCCACCUCGGCCUCCCAAAGUUCGGGGAUUACAGGUGUGAGCCACUGUGCCCGGUCAAUUAUUUUUUCUUAUAGCUAUUAGUGGUGUUUUUGUUUUUUGAGACACAGUCUCGCUCUGUUGCCCAGGCUGGAGGGCAGUGGUGCAAUCUCGGCUCACUGCAACCUCUGCCUCCCGAGUUCAAGUGAGUCUUCCGCCUCAGCCUCCCGAGUAGCUGGGACUACAGGCGCGCGCCACCAUGCCUAGCUAAUUUUUGUAUUAUUAGUAGAGAUGGGGUUUCACCAUAUUGGCCAGGCUGCUCUCAAACUCCUGACCUCGUGAUCCUCCUGCCUUGGCUUCCCAAAGUGCUGGGAUUAUAGGUGUGAGCCACCGCCCCUGGCUGUUAGUGGUAUUUUAAAAAAUUAUGUCUAGGCAUCUAUAAUAAGGCUGUAUGUAUUGGAUUGCUGUGAAGAGUCAAUGAAUUAAUAAAUGCAAAGUACCUCAAACUGUUAUCACAUAAUACAGGUUUAGUAAAAGUUUUCCACUAUUAUCAGUGAUAUACUCAUUAUCAUAAGUAUCUUCAUUAGGAUUUAUGGAAAGGAUUUUAACCAUGUUGUUUACCUUUGGCAAAUUUGUAAUUCAUGGUGGAAAAAGAGAAACACUUGUAAUGAGUAUAACGAAGCCUUUCCCUAUCAUUAUUAUUCAGUGUGGAAUUUUAAAAGGAAGAGAAAAAGUAUGUGUGCAUAGUCUUUGUUCAGACUUUAUCUUUUAUGCUACAUAAAGAAUACCAGUCUGAGGCUGGGCGCGGUGGCUCACACCUGUAAUCCUAGCACUUUGGGAGGCCAAGGUGGGUGGAUCACUUGAGGUCAGGAGCUCGAGACCAGCCUGGCCAACAUGGUGAAACCCCGUCUCUACUAAAAAUACAAAAAAAACAAAAACAAAAACAAAUAGCCAGGCAUGGUGUUGCAUGCCUGUAAUCCUAGCUACUCAAGAGGCUGAGGUGGGAGGAUUGCUUGAACCUGGGAGUUGGAGGUUAUAGUGAGCUGAGAUUGCACCACUGCACACUCCAGACUGGGUGACAGAGCGAGACUCUGUCUUACAAAAUAAAAAAUAAACGGUUACCAAUCUGAAACCCUGAAAAUAUGAUGAGUAGUAGAAAGCACAGCUGUCAAAAAAGCAGGAAGAGAUUAUAAAAUUUUUUCUAAUAUUUCCCCCCAAAAUGCAGAAAACAUACUGGCAACAUUAUUUGACCAGAAGAAGCAGUACAAUAGGAUAACCAUCAAAUAUCUGAUUAUUAAUUCAAUAUUCCCUCUUAAUUAACAUGGGUUAAGGAAUAAAUCCCUAAUAUAUACAUUAUUUAAAUGUACAUGAAAAUGAAAACAAUUGAAAAACCUGUGAGUGGCAGUAAAAGUUGUAUUGGAAGUUUUAUAACCUAAUAUUUGUGCAUAUAUUGUAAUACUAGGAAGAAAAAAUAUAGAACCCAAGGAACUAAAACAAGCUGAAAUGAAUUGUGGGAGGAAGGAGGUAGUAUUAUUUUAAAAGGCAGAAAUAAUUGAAAGAAAAAAACUGGAUCUGAAUCCAAAAUUGAUAUUUGAUGGAAGAGAAAAAAAAUGAGACAAAGUUUAGUGAUUCCAGAGGUGAAAUAAGGAUGACAAAUAAACAAUAUUGUAUAUGAGAAAUUGAAAUGGCUAUAUAUGUAAACUUAAAAGAACUGUGUCAUUUGGGGUAAUGAAAAUGUGGCAUGGGUAAAGGUUGUACAAUUUUGUUUAUAUACUACAGGUCACUCAACUAUACACUUUAAAAGGGUGAAUAUUAUGCUGUGUGAAUUUGAUCUCAAUUUAAAAACUUAAGGCUGGUUGCAGUGGCUCAUGCCUGUAAUUCCAGCACUUUGGGAGGCUGAGGUAGGAGAAUGGCUUGAGGCCAGGAGUUCAAGACCAGUCUAGGUAACAUAAUGAGAUCCCCCUCCCCUCAUCUCUACAGAAAAAAAAAAAAAUUAAAACAACAAACUUAAAAGUUGGUAUUAUAGACAUUUUUAUAAUAUAUCUGAAAAUCUGGAAAAAGUCUGUGAUUUUUAAUAAGUUGACGACAUCAGAAUUAACUGGAGGUGUAAAAUCUUAAUAGACCUCCCUCCAGAAUAAACUUAUUUAAAAAAAUAAGACUGGCCAGGCAUGGUGGCUCACGCCUGUAAUCUCAGCAUUCUGUGAGGCCAAGGCGGGUGGAUCACCUGAGGUCGGGGAUUUGAGACCAGCCUGACCAACAUGGAGAAACCCUGUCUCUACUAAAAAUACAAAAAAUUAGCCGGGCGUGGUGGCUCAUGCCUGUAAUCCCGGCUACUCAGGAGGCUGAGGCAGGAGAAAGGCUUGAACCCGGGAGGCAGAGAUUGCGGUGAGCGGGGAUCAUGCCAUUGCACUCCAGCCUGGGCAACAAGAGUGAAACUCUCUCAAAAAUAAAUAAGUGAAAUAAAAUUUUUCUUAAAAUAUAUUUUAAAUGUCAAAUUGCUACACUAAAAAAGACACCAAGGUAGAGAUUUUUAUAGGUGAAAUCUAUGAAAUGUCUUAGGAAACUCUUCUAGGACAUAGACUGAGAUAGCAAAUUAUCUAUUUUUAAAAUUUGUCAUAAUCCUGAUGUUACAACCUACUAGAACCCAAAACAAUUUGUCCAGAAUCAGUUAUGAAAAUACAGCAUUAUAAAUUAGCAAAUCAAAUCUAGUAACCCAUUGAAAAUAAAUAUUUGUCACAUUCUGAAUUUAGGAAAAAACAAUUCUGAUAAAUCAAACUUUCUACUUUCUGAAACUUGAAAAUCAAAUUGAUUUAGAUAAGAUUGUAUUUCUUAGUGUCUGAACUCAGGAACCAAAUAGAUGUGGAUAGCAUGGGAUUUUUGGAAUACAAGAUAAGAUAAUUUACAUGGGAUUGCAAAAGUUCAAAUAACUAAAGUUCUGUCAAUGAAAAUAUAUGCUCUAACCUCAACAUCUUCUAGAUGAACCCUUUUUUCUAGCAGUAUUUGACAGGAUGGGAUAUAUUUUAUAAAUAAACUUGGACUAUUAUCCUA